GUACGCGGCGCAGCGCGGCAGUCCUGAUGGCCCGGCAUGGGUUACCGCUGCUGCCCCUGCUGUCGCUCCUGGUCGGCGCGUGGCUCAAGCUAGGAAAUGGACAGGCUACUAGCAUGGUCCAACUGCAGGGUGGGAGAUUCCUGAUGGGAACAAAUUCUCCAGACAGCAGAGAUGGUGACGGGCCUGUGCGGGAGGCGACAGUGAAACCCUUUGCCAUCGACAUAUUUCCUGUCACCAACAAAGAUUUCAGGGAUUUUGUCAGGGAGAAAAAGUAUCGGACAGAAGCUGAGAUGUUUGGAUGGAGCUUUGUCUUUGAGGACUUUGUCUCUGAUGAGCUGAGAAACAAAGCCACCCAGCCAAUGAAGUCUGUACUCUGGUGGCUUCCAGUGGAAAAGGCAUUUUGGAGGCAGCCUGCAGGUCCUGGCUCUGGCAUCCGAGAGAGACUGGAGCACCCAGUGUUACACGUGAGCUGGAAUGACGCCCGUGCCUACUGUGCUUGGCGGGGAAAACGACUGCCCACGGAGGAAGAGUGGGAGUUUGCCGCCCGAGGGGGCUUGAAGGGUCAAGUUUACCCAUGGGGGAACUGGUUCCAGCCAAACCGCACCAACCUGUGGCAGGGAAAGUUCCCCAAGGGAGACAAAGCUGAGGAUGGCUUCCAUGGAGUCUCCCCAGUGAAUGCUUUCCCCGCCCAGAACAACUACGGGCUCUAUGACCUCCUGGGGAACGUGUGGGAGUGGACAGCAUCACCGUACCAGGCUGCUGAGCAGGACAUGCGCGUCCUCCGGGGGGCAUCCUGGAUCGACACAGCUGAUGGCUCUGCCAAUCACCGGGCCCGGGUCACCACCAGGACUGGCACAGGCUCAGGACCUGUCCUCACACCAGGCUUCUUUCCAGACCAUGCUCUCCCCAGCCCUCAUGCUCCCUGAUCAUGGCCGGCCCUGCGGAUGAGGCAGGCAAGAUGGGUAAGCCCUAGGCCUUUUUCUCAGGACGUGUCUGUCCUCUCUCCCCUUCUCUGCUGGCAGGAUGGGCAACACUCCAGAUUCAGCCUCAGACAACCUCGGUUUCCGCUGUGCUGCAGACGCAGGCCGGCCGCCAGGGGAGCUGUAAGCAGCCGGGUGGUGACAAGGAGAAAAGCCUUCUAGGGUCACUGUCAUUCCCUGGCCAUGUUGCAAACAGCGCAAUUCCAAGCUCGAGAGCUUCAGCCUCAGGAAAGAACUUCCCCUUCCCUGUCUCCCAUCCCUCUGUGGCAGGCGCCUCUCACCAGGGCAGGAGAGGACUCAGCCUCCUGUGUUUUGGAGAAGGGGCCCAAUGUGUGUUGACGAUGGCUGGGGGCCAGGUGUUUCUGUUAGAGGCCAAGUAUUAUUGACACAGGAUUGCAAACACACAAACAAUUGGAACAGAGCACUCUGAAAGGCCAUUUUUUAAGCAUUUUAAAAUCUAUUCUCUCCCCCUUUCUCCCUGGAUGAUUCAGGAAGCUGACAUUGUUUCCUCAAGGCAGAAUUUUCCUGGUUCUGUUUUCUCAGCCAGUUGCUGUGGAAGGAGAAUGCUUUCUUUGUGGCCUCAUCUGUGGUUUCGUGUCCCUCUGAAGGAAACUAGUUUCCACUGUGUAACAGGCAGACAUGUAACUAUUUAAAGCACAGUUCAGUCCUAAAAGGGUCUGGGAGAACCAGAUGAUGUACUAGGUGAAGCAUUGCAUUGUGGGAAUCACAAAGCAAAUAGUACUCCAGAAAGACAAAUAUCAGAAGCUUCCUAUUCUUUUUUUUUUUUUUUUUUUUUUUGAGACAGGGUCUUUCUCUGUUGCCCAGGCUAGAGUGCACUGGUGAUCACGGCUCACUCUAGCCUUGAAUUCCUGGGCCCAAGCAAUUCUCCCACCUCAGCCUCCUGAGUAGCUGGGACUACAAGUGUGCACCACCAUGCCUGGCUAAUUUUUUGAAUUUUUGUAGUGAUGGGAUCUCGCUCUGUUGCCCAGGGUGGUCUCGAACUCCUGGCCUCAAGCGAUCCUCCCACCUCGACCUCCCAAAGUGCUGGGAUUACAGGUGUGAGCCACCUCGCCUGGGCCCCCUUCUCCAUAUGCCUCCAAAAACAUGUCCCUGGAGAGUAGCCUGCUCCCACACUGUCACUGGAUGUCAUGGGGCCAAUAAAAUCUCCUGCAAUUGUGUAUCUCA